GAUAAGUUGGGACGACCGGACAGCUUCUCAGGUUGCUAAGCGACGAGGCGGGAGCGCACGCACACCCUGGCUGCUUUGUAGCACCUGAGGAAACUGUGGCGGCGGCGGCGGCGUCCUGGAGACCCAAGAGACCAAGCGAGCGUGUCGCUCCCUCUCGGGUCCGAGGACCUAGCCUAGGAACCUUCUGCCCGGGGUAGUGUCUGGUGAUGAGGCGAGAGUUUUGCUGGGACGCCUACUCCAAAGCGGCCGGGAGUCGCGCUUCUUCCCCACUCCCGAGACAGGAUAGAGAUUCCUUCUGCCAUCAGAUGUCUUUCUGCUUGACUGAACUGCACCUGUGGUCUUUGAAGAAUACCUUACACAUUGCGGAUAGAGACAUUGGGAUCUACCAGUAUUAUGACAAGAAAGAUCCACCAGCGACAGAGCAUGGUAACUUAGAAAAGAAGCAGAAGCUGGCAGAGUCACGAGAUUAUCCUUGGACGCUCAAAAACAGACGCCCAGAAAAACUCCGAGACUCGCUCAAAGAGUUGGAGGAGCUGAUGCAAAACAGUCGGUGUGUGCUGAGCAAAUGGAAGAACAAAUAUGUCUGUCAGCUCCUUUUUGGUUCAGGUGUGCUGGUGUCUCUAAGCCUUUCUGGGCCGCAGCUGGAGAAAGUGGUGAUUGACAGAAGCCUGGUGGGGAAGCUCAUCUCAGACACCAUCAGUGAUGCUCUUCUCACAGACAGUUUUAUCAUCUUAUCAUUUUUGGCACAAAACAAACUAUGUUUUAUUCAGUUUACCAAGAAGAUGGAGUCUUCUGAUGUAAACAAAAGACUGGAAAAACUCUCAGCCUUGGAUUAUAAGAUUUUCUAUUAUGAAAUACCCGGCCCAAUAAACAAGACAACAGAGCGACAUCUAGCUAUCAACUGUGUUCAUGAUAGAGUUGUUUGCUGGUGGCCACUGGUCAACGAUGAUGCUUGGCCUUGGGCCCCCAUUUCUUCUGAGAAGGACAGAGCCAAUCUACUCCUCCUGGGUUAUGCUCAAGGAAGACUAGAGGUUCUGAGUUCUGUCCGCACAGAAUGGGACCCACUGGAUGUUCGCUUUGGCACCAAACAGCCUUAUCAGGUGUUCACAGUGGAGCACUCCGUAAGUGUAGACAAAGAGCCCAUGGCUGACAGCUGCAUCUAUGAAUGCAUUCGGAAUAAAAUCCAGUGUGUGUCAGUCACCAGAAUACCACUAAAGUCAAAGGCCAUCAGCUGCUGCAGGAAUGUUACUGAAGACAAACUGAUUCUGGGCUGUGAAGAUUCUUCGCUAAUUCUUUAUGAAACUCACCGUAGAGUGACUCUCUUAGCACAGACUGAACUUUUGCCUUCAUUAAUAAGCUGCCACCCAAGUGGUGCCAUUCUGCUAGUUGGCAGCAACCAAGGGGAGUUGCAAAUUUUUGAUAUGGCUCUAUCCCCUAUUAACAUCCAACUGUUGGCUGAAGACCGCUUACCCAGGGAGACUCUGCAAUUCAGUAAAUUAUUUGAUGCCUCCAGCAGUCUUGUUCAAAUGCAAUGGAUAGCUCCUCAGGUUGUUUCUCAGAAGGGUGAAGGUAGUGAUAUCUAUGAUCUCCUCUUCCUCAGGUUUGAAAGAGGACCUUUGGGUGUGCUGUUGUUUAAACUAGGCGUCUUCACUCGAGGACAGCUGGGCCUGAUAGACAUCAUCUUCCAGUACAUUCACUGUGAUGAGAUCUAUGAGGCAAUAAACAUCCUGAGCAGCAUGAACUGGGACACUCUGGGCCACCAGUGCUUUAUCAGCAUGAGCGCCAUUGUAAACCAUCUUCUUAGACAGAAGCUCACUCCAGAGAGAGAAGCACAGCUUGAGACAAGCCUUGGAACCUUCUAUGCUCCAACAAGACCACUUCUGGAUUCCACUAUAUUGGAAUAUAGAGAUCAAAUCAGCAAAUAUGCAAGGAGAUUCUUCCAUCACUUGCUCAGGUACCAGAGGUUUGAAAAGGCAUUUCUCCUAGCUGUUGACGUUGGUGCUCGUGACCUCUUUAUGGAUAUUCAUUACCUUGCACUAGAUAAAGGUGAAUUGGCACUAGCUGAAGUGGCAAGAAAAAGAGCUAGUGACAUUGAUGCAGAAUCAAUAACCUCUGGGGUUGCCAAAGGGACCAAUUGUCAGCUUCUCUCUGAUGCCACCACAUAGAUCUAAUCUUCAAGGUGGUACUGAAGGACUCAAAGCCAUUCCAGCAGGGUAGCUCUAAACCUGAAUACCAGGGCUGACAGGUACUAGCAAGAUAAUCCCAUUCUCCUUCCCCCAUCCUGAAAGAGUUCCAGAUUGAUUAGACCACUUUCAUAUCUCUGUUUCUAAUGGAUAGGGAAUACUCACUAUUAAUGCAGUAUUGGAUAAGAAUAACUGUAAUUGACCUAUCACUAUAUCUUGUUACUUUCUAGGGAGGGAUAUUAAUGUGUGUACUACUACUAAUAAUAGCACUUAAUAUUUAUUGAAUGUUAAGUUACAGAUAACUAAUUUUCACCACAACUCUGUGAAGUAAGUACAAUUUAUAUUUGCUAUGAGAAGUCACUUCUAACUAAAUGAUGAAAGCAUACCAUGUUUAUAGGAAUGAUGACGUUAUAUGAUGGGGAAAUAUCCUCCAUCCCUAUCCCUCUAGCCAUUUAGGAAAACAAAGCAGGAAGUUAAGUCCUAACCAAUUUUCUGGGAAUUUUCCUUAGUUGUCCUGUACCCUGCCUUUUAUUCCAGGGUAUCAGAUAUAAUGAGGGCCAUCUUUGCAUUUUAAAGCUAUUUAAAAUUAGUAAGAGUGAAAGAGAAUGUGAAGAGAUUAUCACAAAAUUUCAGCAAAAUGAAGAAACUCCCCAAUUCACCAAAAUGCAUCUCACUUCCUGUGUAUUCUCUGAUGAGGUUACUGUGGCCAGCGGAUAAUUCCUAGCCAGAAAGCUUAGUGUACCCACUUUGAGCCCUGCGUCAUUUCUAGCAAAUAUAUUUUCACUGAUACCCUGUGACUUCCCUUUUCUCAGCCUUGUCUCAGGCCUCAGCCUUUGACCUAGAUUACUAUGUUUUGACAAAGAUACUAUUAAAUAACAUCAGUAACUUUCAAGAGGUUGCCCUAUUACAUGAAUGUUCUACUCCAGUUUUGCUGCAGAAAACUGGGUGAUUCUCACUCAUAAUUCCGAAUGGAAUUAACAAAGAAUUUCUUGUUUCCUCAUCAUGGUCUCUACCUAGUUCUUUUUUGCAGCCCACAUCAUGCUGGGGAAAGCUAAUUUUCUUUCAAAUUCCCUCAAUUUAAUUCAAUUAUUCUCUUAAACUUAUCCCAAAGCUGAAAGUUAUUAAAUUUUUGGCUUUCAAAGUGGUUCUUUGAUGCAAGCAAGGAGCCAAAUUAUGUGAGAUAGCAAAAGAGUAGUUCCAUUUACAUGGGAAAGUCUGUAAAAAAGCAUCAGACAUAAAUACUGCCACCAUAGUUAAAAGCAAGAGGCGCCAAAGGAAAAGCUGGAUGAUGAUAAUCUGAACAAUUUGGUAAUUUUUUAAACUUUUUAUUGAAGUCUAACAUGCAUACAGAAAAGUGCACAAAACAUAAGCAUGUGACUCAAUGAAUUUCACAAAGUGAACACAUCCUUGUAAACAGUAUCCUGACCAAGUAACAUAUGUUACCAGGACCCCAGAAGCCUUCCUAUACCCACUUCAAGAUGCUAUAAUCUCAGCCCAGCUGUCCAGAUUUGUAACAUUAUAGACUAAUUUGCCUUUUUUCAAACUUAAAUGGAUUCAUACCUAUAUUCUUUUGUAUUUGGCUCCUUUUAUUCAACAUUAUGAAUCUGAGAAUCUUUCGUAUGUUGCAUAUAGUUAUAAUUCUUCCACUCUUCUUGCUGUAUAACAAUAUUCCAAUGCAUGAAUGUACUUCAAUUUAUUCUACUUUAGAUGGAUAUUUGGGUUGUUUCAAGUUUGGGGCUAAUGCGAAUAGUGUUGCUAUGAACAUUCUUGUGUAUGUCUUUUAAUGGACAUAGGUAGGCAGAUCUGUUUGACUGUGCUUAGAAGUUGAACUCCUGUGACGUAGGAUAUGCAGCCUUAGUAGCUACUUCCAGUUUUCCAAAGUAGUUGUUAACAAUUUCCCUUCUCACCAGCAGUAUGUAAGAGUUCCAGUUUUGGCCAUCCUCAAUGAUGCUUGAUAUUGUCUCUCUUUUUUAUUUUAGCCAUUCCGGUGGAAAAGGUAUUGUAAUUUUGUAUAUGUGACAGUAUAAUAUAUAGGCUGUUUCUGGAUCAUGUUCUAUUUUAUUACUCUGUUUGUCUAUACUUGCACAAAUAUCUCACUGCUUUAAGCAACUCUGGCUGUCAAUGUUAUUAUUUAGUAGUGAAAAUUGCCCAGCUUUGUUCUUUAAGAUAGACUUGGCUAUCCUUCCAUAUAAAUCUCAAAAUCAGCUUAUACCCUGACUCACUCAAGGAAAAAAAAGAAACAAAAACAGUGGGGGCUGAAAUUCUGGUUAGAAUCUCAUUUAAUUCAUAGAUACAUUUGGGCUGAAUUUAUUUCUUUAUAAUAUUGUUUUCCAAUCCAUGAAUAUGAUCUAUCCCUCCAUUUAUUUAGGUCUUCUCUAUUUCUUAUGAAAAAUGUUUUGUAGUUUUCAUAGUAGUGGUCUUCCACAUCUUCCUUUAGAUUUAAGUAUUUCUUUUUCUCCUUUGUAUGUGGUAAUCUUAUUUUUAAAUUUCAUUUUCUGUUUUAUUUCUGGUAUAUAUACAAUUGACUGUUGUAUAUAUUGACCUUAUAUCUAGCAAUAAGUGAUAAAUUCGCUUAUUAAUGCCAACAGUUAGUAAAUUCUUUUGAAUUUUCUGCAUCCACAUCAUGUCGUCUGGAAAUGUGUUAGUCUCUUUGCAUUGCUAUAAAGGAAUACCUGAGACUGAGUAAUUUAUAAAGAAAAAAGGUUUAUUUUGGUUCAAGGUUCUUCAGGCUAUAUGAGAAGUAUGGUGCUGGCAUCUGUACCUGGUGAGGCCUCAGGAAGCUUCAAAUCAUGGUAGAAGGUAAAGGGGGAGAUGCCAUAUCACAUGGUAAGAGGGGAAGAAACAGAGAGAGGAGGAGGACCCAGGCUCCUGUAAACAACUAGCUCUCAUGUGAACUAACAGAGCAAGAACUCAGUUCUUACCAUGGGGAGGGCACCAAGCCAUGUAAGAGGGAUCUGCCUUCAUGACCCAAACACCUCCCAUGAGGCCCUACCUCCAACAUGGGGGAUUACAUUUCAAUAUGAGAGUUGGAGGGGACAAACAUCCAAACCAUAUCAGCAAAUAAGGACAUUUUAAUUCCUUCCUUUCUAGUUCUUAUGCUUUUUACUUCUCUUUCCUUAUUAUUGCACUGACUAGAAGCUCUAGUAUAAAGAUAAGUAGAAGUUGUGACCGGCAUUAUUUUCUAUUUCUUGAUUCUUAGGGAAAGCUUUCAAUAAUUCACCAGUUAGCAUAAAGUUUUCCCCAGGUUUUUAAUAAACCUUUUAUUCAUAUUAAUAAAGUUCCCUUCAGUAACUAGUUUGCUAAGAGUUUCUAUCAUGAAUAGGUAUUGAAUUUUAUCGAAUACUUCUCCUGUGCCUAUCAAGAUUAUCAUGAUCUUUCUCCUUUGUUCUAUUAAUAUCGUGAAUUGCAUUGAUUUUCAAAUGGCAAACUAACCUUACGUUCCAGAAUAAAUACUUCUUAAUUGUGAUGAUGUAUUUUUACAUAUUCCUGCAUUUCAUUUACUAUUUUUAAAUGUUGGCAUUUACAUUCAUGAGGGAUCAGACUUACAGACUCAUGGUUUUGCUUCAAUAUCUCUGCCUAGUUUUGAUAUCUAGAUUAUUUUGACCUAAUGCCUAAAUGUCAAACAUCUAGAAAGGAUACAUUUGAACAUGUAAUAGUACUUUAUGAUCCAGCUCUUUAUAUAUGGCAUAUGUAACACUUCCUACAACUUAAAAAUUUUACAUUAAUCUUGACUGUAUUAAUGUGAAUAUUUUGGUUGUAACAUUGUAUUAAAUUUUUGUAAAAUAUUAUCAUUGGAAGAAACUGGAUAAAAGAGACAUGGGACUUCUCCAUUAUUUCUUAGAACUGCAUAUUAAUAUAUAAUUAUCUUUAAAAGUUUAAUUUUUAAAGUUUAUAUUAAUAUAGUGUCCUAUGUUAAGUACUGUGACAAACAUUACCUUAUUUGGUCCUCCCAAAUUAUCUCUAAAGGAGAAACUACUGUAUUGGUGAAUUUUUUAGAAGUUUUUUUCUUUAAUAAUUUCAACUUUUAUUUUAGCUUCAGGGGGCAUAUGUGCAGGUUUGUUACAUGGGUAUAUUGCAUGAUGCUAAGAUUUGGGGUAUGAAUGAUCCCCAUCACCCAGGUAGUAAGCAAUAGUACCCAAGAAGUAGUUUUUCAGCCCUUGCUCCUUGCCCUUCUAUUAGUCCCCAGUGUUUAUUAUUCCCAUCUUUAUGUCCAUGUGUACCUAAUGCUUUACUCCCACUUACAUAUGAGAAUAUGUGGUAUUUGGUUUUCUAUUACUGAGUUAAUUCACUUACAGUAAUGGCUUCCAGCUACAACUAUGUUGCUGCAAAGGAUGUUAUUUCAGUCUUUUUUAUGGCUGUAUAGUUUUCCAUGGUGUAUAUAUACUACAUUUUCUUCAUUCAAUCCAUCAUUGAUGGGUUCCUAGGUUGAUUCCAUGUCUUUGCUAUUGUGAGUAGUGCUGUGAUGAACAUACAAGUGCAUGUGUCUUUUUGGCAAAACAAUUUAUUUUCCUUUGGGUAUAUACUCAGGAAUGGGAUCAACGGGUUGAAUGAUAGUUCUCAGUUUUUGAGAAAUCUCCAGACUGUUUUCCACAGUGGCUGAAUUAAUUUACAUUCCCACCAGCAGUGUAUAAGCAUUCCCUUUUCUCCACAACCUCACAGCAUAUGUUAUUUUCUGACUUUUUAACAAAAGCCAUUCUGACUGGUGUGAGAUGGUAUCUCAUUGUGGUUUUGAUCUGCAUCUCUUUGAUUAGUGACAUUGAGCAUUUUUUCAUGUUUGUUGACUGCUUGUAUGUCUGCUUUUGAGUAAUGAUUGUUCAUGUCAUUUUCAUGCUUUUUAAUGGACUUAUUUGUUUUUAUCUUGUUGAUUUCAAGUUUUUCAUAGAUUCUGCUUAUUAGUCCUUUGUUAAAUGCAUAGCAUAGUUUGCAAAUAUUUUCUCUCAUUCUGUAGGCUGUCUGUUUACUUUGUUGAUAGUUUUUUUGAUGUGCAGAAGCUCUUUGGUUUAAUUGGGCCCCACUUGUCAAUUUUUGUUAUUGUUGCAUUUAUUUUUGAGGACUUACUUAAUCAUAAAUUUUUUACCAAGGCCAAUGUCCAGAAGGACAUUUCCUAGGUUUUCUUCUAGGAUUCUUAUAUGGUAUGAGGUCAUACAUUUAAUUAUUUAAUUAAUCUUAAGUUAAUUUUUGUAUAUGGUGAAAAGAUAUGGCUAGCAAGCUAUUCCAGAACCAUUUAUUGGAUAGGGAGUCCUUUCCCAACUUCUUUUCUUGACUGUCGAAGAUCAGAUGCCUGUAGAUGUGUGGCUUUAUUUCAGUGUUCUCUAUUUUGUUACAUUGGUCUCUGUGUCUGUUUUUGUACUACUACUAUGUUGUUUUGGUUACUGCAGACUUGUAGUAUAGUUUAAAGUUGGGUAAUGGUGAUCCCUCCAGCUCUGUUCUUCAUGCUUAGGAUUGCUUUGGUUAUCUGGGCUCUUUUUUGGUUCCAUAUGAAUUUUAGAAUGGUUUUUGUUCUAUUUCUAUGAAAAAUGACCUUGGUAGUUUGAUAGAUACAGAGUUGAAUCCAUAGAUUGCUUUGGGCAGUAUGGACAUUUUAAUGAUAUUGAUUUUUCCAAUCCAGGCACGUGGAAGUUUUUCCAUUUGUUGGUGUCGUCUGUGAUUUCUUUCAGCGGUAUUUUGUAGUUCAUUCACUUCCUUGGUUAGGUGUAUUCCUAUGUAUUUUAUUUUGUUUGUGUAUUGAUAUUGUAAGUGGGAUUAUGUUCUUGACUUGGCUCUCAGCUUGAAUGUUAUUAGUAUACAGAAAUGGCACUGAUUUUUCUGUUGAUUUUUGUAUCCAAAACUUUACAGAAGUCAUUUUUCAGGUCUAGGAGUCUUCUGGUGAAGUCCUUAGGGUUUUCUAUGUACAGAAUCAUAUCAUCAGCAAAGAGAGAUAAUCUUUUCCUAUUUGGAUGCCUUUAAUUUCUUUCUCUUCUCCUGAUUUCUCUGGCUAGGACUUCCAGUACUUUUUUGAACAGGAAUGAUGAGUGUGGGCAUCUUUGUCUUAUUCCUGUUCUUAAGGGGAAUGCUUCCAGCUUUUGCCAUUUAGUAUGAUGUUGGCUAUGGGUUUGUCAUAGAUGGCUCUUACUUUGAGGUCUGUUCCUUCUAUGCCUAGCUUGUUGAGGGUUUUUUAUCAAGGAGGAUGUUGGAUUUUAUCAAAGGCUUUUUCCAUGUCUAUUGAGAUAAUCAUAUGGUUUUUGUUUUUAAUUCUGUUCAUGUGGUGAAUCACGCUUAUUGAUCUGCAUAUGUUGAACCAACCUUGCAUCCCAAGAGUAAAGCCUGCUUGAUCAUGGUGAAUUAACUUUCUGAUUUGCUGCUGGAUUCAAUGUGUUAGAAUUUUGUUGAGGAUUUUUGCAUUUAUGUUCAUCAGGCAUAUUGGCCUGUGGUUUUCUUUUUUCAUUGUGUCUUUGCCAGGUUUUGGUAUCAGGGUGGUUCUGGCUUCAUAGAAUGAGUUAUGAAGGAGUUCCCUCCUACCUGAUUUUUGGAAUAGUUUCAGUAGGAUUGGUACAAGUUCUUCUUUAUACAUCUAGUAUAAUUCAGCUGCAAAUCCAUCUGGUCCGGGGCUUUUUAAAAAUUGGUAGGCUUUCUGGCUAGGCACGGUGGCUCACGCCUGUAAUCCCAGCACUUUGGGAGGCCGAGGUGGGCAGAUCAUGAGGUCAGGAGAUCGAGACCAUCCUGGCUAACACGGUGAAACCCCGUCUCUACUAAAAAUACAAAAAAUUAGCCAGGCAUGAUGGUGAGUGACUGUAGUCCCAGCUACCUGGGAGGCUGAGGCAGGAGAAUGGCAUGAACCCAGGAGGCAGAGAUUGCAGUGAGCCGAGAUCAUGCCACUGCACUCCAGCCUCGACGACAGAGCGAGACUCUGUCUCAAAAAAAAAAAAAAAAAAAAAAAGGUAGGCUUUUUAUUAUUGAUUGAAUUUCAUAACUUGUUUAUUGUUCUGUUCAGGGUUUCACUUUCUUUCUGGCUCAAUCUUGGGAGGUUGUGUGUUUCCAGGAAUUUAUCUAUUUCCUCUACAUUUUCUAGUUCAUGUGCAUUCAGAUGUUUGUAUUAGUUUCUAAGGAUCUUUUGUAUAUCUGUGGGAUCACUGAUAAUAUUACCUUUGUCAUUUCUGAUUGUGCUUAUUUAGAUCAUCCUUUUUUCCUUUGUUAUCAAAUGAGUGGUCUAUCAUACCUGUUUAUCCUUUCAAAGUAUAAACUUUUGGUGUCGUUCAUUCUUUGUAUGGAUUUUUGGAUCUCAAGUUCAUUUAGUUCUGCUCUGAUAUUAGUUACUUCAUUUCUUCUGCUAUCUUUGGGGUUAGUUUAUUCUUGUUUUUCUAGUUCCUCUAGGUGUGAUGUUAGAUUGUUAAUCUGAGAUCUUUCUAACUUUUUGGUGCAGGCGUUUAGUUCUAUAAACUUUGGAGAGAUCUUUUUUGUAUAGGCAAUGAAAUGAGGUUACAGUGGAAAUGCUCCAUAAAUUGCAAAAAAUUGAGAGCCAGUGCUCUAUAGCAAUUCUAAUCAGUUUUCUAUGGAUAUAGUUCCCAGAUUGAACUCCUUAAUAUAAUAGUGCCAUAAAACACUCAGUAAAAUAAAAUAUAUAUGGCUAAAUACUUGAAGGAUAUAUUAAGACAAACUAAUUUCUUUAAAAAUUUCUGGUGUACAUGAAAUGUUCUCAGAAAUCACAAACUUAACUGUUUGUUUAUCUUAACAUUUCCAAAAAUUUUGACCAUACAACCCUCAUCUUUCUCAUUGUUCUAGGCAAGAGCUAUAAAUUCACAGAACUUGAGAUUUUUAUAAUUCACAUGGGGAAACUUAUAGCUUAAUUGCACAGCUGUAAAUCUUUAUCCUUACUAAUAGGCUUAGCAUGAUGGUACUAGCCAUUAAAAUAGUAAUAAUCAUUCAAUUGAGGUAAAGAACUCAGAUAUUUAUACUGCUAUUAUAGUAGUCUCCCCUUAUCUGCUAAUUUCCUUUCUGUGGUAUCAAUUACCUGCAGUCAACCACAGCCCAAAAAUAUUAUAUGGAAAAUUCCAGAAAUAAAUAAUUCAUAAUUUUUAAAUCGUGCACUGUUGAGUAGUGUGAUGAAAUCUCACACUGUCCUAUUUUGUUUUGUCCAGGAUGUGAAUCCCUUUGUCCAGUGUACCCACACUGUAUAUGCCACCUGCCCAUAAGUCACUUAGCAGCCAUCUUGGUUAAAAGAUGGACUGUAAUGGUGUAGCACUGCUUGUAUUCACGCAACCUGUAUUUUACUUAAUAAUGACUCCAAAGCACAAAAGUAGUGAUGCUGGCAAUUCAGAUAUAACAAAGAGAUGCAUCUUAUGGUGCUCUCAGUGAGUAAAAAGGUGAAAGUUCUCAACUUAAUAAGGAUAUAUAUCAUAUGCGGAGCUUGCUAAGAUCUAUGGUACAUUACAUAUGAAUCCUCUAUCCAUGACAUUGUGAAGAAGGAAACAGAAAUUCAUGAGUUGUGCUGUUGCACCUCAAACUGCAAAAGUUACAGCCACAGUGUGUGAUAAGUGCUUAGCUACGAUGGAAGUCAUUACAUUUGCAGGUGAAAGACACAAACAGAAAGGUGUUCGAAUUGACAGCCAUCAGAUUCGGUAAUAUCUGCUAUUUCAAGCAUUCACUGGGGGUCUUUGAACAUAUACCCCAUGGAUAAAGGAAGACUACCAUACCUGGAAAAUUCCUCUCCCCUCAGCCUCUUCCUUCUUUCAGUUCCACACUCUGAGUGACAUACAGCCAAAUUUCAGAAUAGGAAGCUCUUUGUCCUUGUUACCCCACAGUUAACAUAAAAAAUCAGAGGUAAAGACAUGUGCAGCUGGUAAUGUCUCAGACUUUCUUGACAAAACUGGAGAGAUUAAAUAAGCAUUCUCAUGAGGGGUUAUAUUGCCAAAACCCAUGAUCACUGUAGAGGCUAGAUAAACAUCUUUAUUAGGGAUUAUCUAUGCUACAGGCAUUGUCUAAAGAACUUGCUGCAGAACACCUUGGUAUGUAGGAGUCAAACAUCCGUCAUCAUGUCAGUUUUGCUUCAAGAUGACAUCACUGUUGCCAUGCAACAGGCCAUUUUCUUACAGAAAUUAAGGCAUUCAAAAGCAGCCAUGUAUACAGGGGAAUUGAGAAAGCCACACACAGGCCCAGUCAACACACAUUUCAGAAAAGACCUGACAAGACCAUAAGCUUUUACCUCAGGCCAAUUCCUAUGCUCAGAGCAAACCUAGCUAAUUAGUGGGACUGUCCCGGCACACAGCUAGUCUGCAAAGACCGGGAAAGAUGGCUUUUUCAAAUGCCCAGUUUCACACACACACACCCCACAAGGCAUACAAAGAAACAGGAAAACAUGGCCUAUUCAAAGGAGCAAAAUUAAUUGGUAGAAAUCAAACCUGAGAAAGCACAGACAUCUUACUAACUAGGCAAAGUCUUUAAAACAGCUGCCUUAAAUAUGUUCAAAGAGUGAAAGGAAACCAUAUAAAGAACUAAAGAAUAUUAAAAAAAAAACACAUAAGAACAAAAUGAAAA